AUUCGGUUUGCAGCAACCGGAGCUGAAACUUUGCAACCCGAGCGCGCACGCUCUGCGCUCGGCCCUGCCAGGGCGGCACGGGAGGGCGGCGCAGGAGGUGGGACCUGCGCCGGGAAGGCUCCGGGACGCCAGCGCACGCGGAGCGGGGACCCCGGAGAGCCAGCAGGCGAGAAGACCGGCCGAGGGAGAGCCGAUCGCGCCUCGAGAGAUCCGAGGAAGUGGUCGCGGGCCGGGAGGCUCCCGUGCCGAGCCGAGGCCAGGGGUCUGGGGUCGCAGCCCGGCGUGCCUGCAGCUGCCGUCGCUCGGGAGCAGCAGCUGUGCCCGGGAUCCCGGCGGCGGCGGGGGAAGGAGGAGCUGCAGCUGGACUGUGGCAGCUGGAGGGAGAGGGCCGGGCUCCCCUGGCGGAGCCGCGCUGGGACGACUGGCUGACCGCGGCCAUGCAGUCUUGACGGAGUCGCUCGGGCGCAGGGGAGCAGCCGCGGGCGCGCCCUCCCGGGAAGGGGCACCGGAGCGCAGGCAGCAGCACUUUAUCUGCGACUCUCCAGCCCAGCGAGAGGCGAAGCGGUUUACCAUGGAACCCGUGACCAAGUGGAGCCCCAAACAAGUGGUGGACUGGACUAGAGGGUUGGAUGACUGCCUGCAACAAUAUGUCCACAAGUUUGAACGAGAGAAGAUCAACGGCGAGCAGCUGCUGCAGAUUUCCCAUCAGGACCUGGAGGAGCUGGGGGUCACACGGAUUGGACACCAGGAGCUUGUGUUGGAGGCUGUGGACCUUCUCUGUGCACUGAAUUAUGGCCUCGAAACUGAUAACAUGAAGAACUUGGUUCUGAAACUGAGAGCAUCUUCCCACAAUUUACAGAAUUACAUAAGUAGCCGACGGAAAAGUCCCGCUUACGAUGGCAACACCUCCCGCAAGGCCCCCAAUGAGUUCCUGACCUCGGUGGUGGAGCUCAUCGGCGCCGCCAAGGCCCUGCUGGCGUGGCUGGACCGGGCUCCGUUUACAGGGAUCACUGAUUUCUCAGUCACGAAGAACAAAAUUAUCCAGCUUUGCUUGGACCUGACCACUACAGUCCAGAAGGAUUGCUUUGUAGCGGAAAUGGAGGAUAAAGUUUUAACUGUGGUCAAGGUUUUAAAUGGCAUCUGUGACAAAACAAUCCGAUCUACCACAGAUCCUGUGAUGAGCCAGUGUGCAUGUCUGGAGGAAGUUCACUUACCAAACAUUAAACCUGGGGAAGGCCUGGGCAUGUACAUCAAAUCAACCUAUGAUGGGUUACACGUGAUUACUGGAACCACAGAAAAUUCUCCUGCAGACAGAUCUCAGAAGAUUCAUGCUGGUGACGAAGUCAUUCAAGUUAAUCAGCAAACUGUGGUGGGAUGGCAGCUGAAAAAUCUGGUGAAGAAAUUGAGAGAGAAUCCCACCGGAGUUGUGUUACUGCUUAAGAAGCGCCCCACCGGGUCUUUCAACUUUACUCCUGCUCCCCUGAAAAACCUACGGUGGAAGCCACCUCUUGUACAGACCUCACCUCCACCCGCGACAACCCAGUCCCCUGAAAGCACUAUGGAUACCUCACUGAAGAAGGAGAAGUCAGCCAUCCUGGAUCUUUAUAUUCCUCCUCCGCCUGCUGUUCCCUACUCUCCCCGGGAUGAGAAUGGCAGUUUUGUUUAUGGAGGGUCCAGUAAGUGCAAACAACCAUUGCCUGGUCCUAAGGGUUCAGAGUCCCCGAAUUCCUUCUUGGACCAGGAAAGCCGGAGACGAAGAUUCACCAUUGCAGACUCGGAUCAGUUGCCUGGGUACUCGGUGGAAACCAACAUUCUGCCCACAAAAAUGAGAGAGAAAACACCAUCUUAUGGCAAGCCACGGCCUUUGUCCAUGCCUGCUGAUGGGAACUGGAUGGGGAUUGUGGACCCUUUUGCCAGACCUCGAGGUCAUGGCAGGAAAGGGGAGGAUGCCCUUUGCCGGUAUUUCAGUAACGAGCGGAUUCCUCCGAUCAUUGAAGAGAGCUCCUCUCCCCCAUACCGGUUCUCCAGACCCACGACCGAGCGGCAUCUGGUCCGGGGUGCGGACUACAUCCGAGGAAGCAGGUGCUACAUCAACUCAGAUCUCCACAGCAGCGCCACGAUUCCAUUCCAGGAGGAAGGGACCAAAAAGAAAUCUGGCUCCUCAGCUACGAAGUCCUCGUCCACAGAACCGUCCCUCCUGGUCAGCUGGUUUACGCGCCUCAAACUGUUGACUCACUGAGAGGGACCCUGCUCAGGCCACCUGCCUGGCUCCUGCCCCAAGUGCCUUGCUUUUACAGUGGACAGCCUCUUCUCGUUUCAGCCUCAGUAUUAUGUAGGGACCUUAUGCAAUUUCUUUUUCUUUUGAAAAGUUAUCUACUGCCCUUCUUGGAAGUUUGCAGGAUUGGAUGGGAACAAAUUCAGAGGAUCUUAGGUGCUGGCUUGUGGAGACAAAAGGAGGGAAAUGGGUAGAGCCUGUUUGUCUUGCUUCCCCAGAGAUAGAAUGUGAAGACACGCGCUAGAAAUCGCAGUCCUGGCCAGAGACGUUAUGGUCAUUGUGAGGGACUGGUGGCAUUGUUCCUUUUUGAGGGGCUGGGGGGACUCAAAUUGGUGGCUGUUUUCACACAGAUGUGUUGGUUUGUGGUCCAACUUCUUUAUCUGAAAAAGCCAGUGAGAAAACAUUUUUGAUUUGAUUUUUCUAAACUAUCUACCAUAUUUUAAGUGUAGCAGCUUUGACUUUGCAAUAACGUGGCAAGUAUCUGAUUUCUCCUUUGAGGCAGAGGUUUAAGUGUAGGCCUGUUACACUUGUUUGAUACCUUUUUCAUGACAGUCUCAGUAUAGAUCAGUUGGUACAGAAAUACAUGAACACAUUUUGAUAGGGCUUAUUUCACACAAAGAAGUUUAUGGUUAUUUGUGUGGGGUGGUGUUGUUAUAUAUUAUUGUCUUUAAGGGAAAAGAAGCUAUAAGAUUCGCUGACAGCCAAAGUAUCAUUUAGAAAAGUGAAGCAACAAGAUUUAGGUUGAUGAAAGAUACAUGAGUUUGCAUUUUGACCUGUUCAGUGUCUGUCUUCCAGCACGGUGUGUACACUUCUUCAAAAUUGUACACAGUUUGCUAAUUAGAAAUAUCUUGGAAAGCCUCAUGGUCACUAAUUUUCAACUAGCAUCAGGUAUUUUGAAAACGUGUGUCUGGAUAUUAACUCUUGUUUAAACUGAAUGUAUGAUAUUUUGUUAGAAUGGAAAAGUACUAUCUUGUUAAUUUAAGUAUUUUAAAUAUAGUUGUAUAUUUUUCUUACUCUUAGUCACCUGUAAUUGAAAUAUUUCUGUUUUGCGUCAUACACGAAGCUAGUGAAAAAGAAAGUGCAAGGCAUUUUCAGAUGAGCAAGUGACUAUCGUGGCUGUUGCCAGCAGGGCAGUAUUGUUAAAAAAAAUCAAAAUAAACCCUCCCAAGCAUUUUGGGAUUUUAUGGAUUAGAAAUGGAAGAACAGGAGAAGCAUAUGCAAAGUGAAAUUGCACGAGGGGAAUUUUCUGAGGUAUCUUCCUAGGCAGAGCCGAAAUCUCCUACUCCAAAAUGCCCUUUCUCAUACCACCGGAAUUGUUGAGUUUGCUGAACUGCCUGGAAUUCAGCCCAUGAAAAUCACUGGAGUUAGGAAACAUCUUCCCUUUAAAAUGCUUCUGGUGUGGUUAAAGGAACUAGCAACCACUCAUGUAUAAUUACUGUGACUGAAUUCAGUCAGGCUGGUUUUUUUUGUUUGUUUGUUUGUUUUUGAGAUGGAGUCUCAAUCUGUCACCCAGGCUGGAGUGCAGUGGCGCAAUCUCAGCUCACUGCAACCUCCACCUUCCAGGUUCAAGCGAUUCUCCUGCCUCAGCCUCCCAUGUAGCUGGGAUUAUAGGUGCCCGCCACCAUGCCUGGCUAAUUUUUGUAUUUUUAGUGGAGACGGGGUUUCACUACGUUGGCCAGGCUGGUCUCAAACUCCCAACCUCAACUGAUCUGCCGGCCUCAGCCUCCCAAAGUGCUGGGAUUACAGGCAUGAGCCACCACACCCGGCUCAGUCUGGCUGUUUUCUUCUCUACCUCUAAGACAACUGCCAUGAAGAUCUGGUAUUUCGGCCUGGCGCAGUGGCUCAUGCCUGUAAUUCCAGAACUUUGGGGGGCCAAGGUGGGUGGAUUACCUGGGGUCAGGAGUUCAAGACCAGCCUGGCCAACAUGGUGAAACCCUGUCUCUACUAAAAAUCAGCUUCGCAUGGUGGUGGGCACCUGUAGUCCCAGCUACUCGGGAGGCUGAGGCAGGAGAAUCACUUGAACCCUGGAGGCGGAGGUUGUAGUGAGCCAAGAUCAGGCCACUGCACUCCAGCCUGGGUGACAGAAGGAGACUCUGUCUCAAAAAAAAAACAAAAAGAAAAAGAUCUGGUAUUUCAUGGAGACAUGGAGACCCAAGGGUGUUUGGCAGAUGGAGAGAAGAGGCUUGCAGUGUGUGACCACAGGGUGUUCAACACACUAGGAGGGUGGGGUGUGGGCUGGGGAGGUCUCGUGUAGGGCACUGGUGAUGAGGAGGGAGCUGUGUACGAGGGGCGAGCCAGCCCUGCCUGUUUUACUCUUGUCUUGAGCUGGCUUUAUGCCCAGGAAGUGGGUGGCAACAUCUCCUCUUACUCCCCAGAUUGUGGGGAGAACUCUAAGAGCUGUAGUUCCACUGGAUGAUGAGUUAAAUCACUCUGGAGGCCUUAGCUGGCUGGUGAGCUCUUUUUCUGUGGGGAAAAUGCCACUUGUGAAUUGAACAGCCAUCCUUUAAGUGAAUAUUCGGCAGUCAGUCUUCAUUAUAGGCAGUGGCCAACCAGAUUGGUGCUUUUCAGCCUUUGUUCCCUGGAGUCCCAGGACCCGCGAGAGAAGUUCCUGGCUCCUCUACUUGCAGUCACCCUCCACAGCUUCAUCUUUCUUUUUAUUUGAGGUUUUCUCCUGAAUUGUGUUUGAAAAAUAUAUUGCUGCUAAAAAAAAAAAACCUUUGUAAACCUCUACUAUGGACAUACAUAAAUAAUAGUUUAAUAUGGAUUUCUUAGAAAUUAAUGGAAACUGCUUGCCUCAGUAGUAAUCCAGGUUUAAUUGUGGACGUGUGUUCACAUAUGAAGUUGCUUGAUGAUGCUUUUUGACAGGAUUCUUUAUUUUUAUUUCUUUAAAAAAAAUUUUUUUUUUUUUCUGAGACAGAUUCUCACUCUGUCACCCAGGCUAGAGUGCAGUGGUACAAUCUCAACUCACUGCAGCCUCUGCCUCCCAGGUUCAGGCAAUUCUCCUGCCUCAGCCUCCCAAGUAGCUGGGAUUACAGGUGCCCGCCACCACACCUGGCUAAUUUUUGUAUUUUUAGUAGAGAUGGAGUUUCACCAUGUUGGCCAGGCUGAUCUUGAACUCCUUGACAGGAUACUUUACAAGAGUGAUUGUUAAAACUCUCCCAGACACAACUCAACACCUACCCCUAUUAUAAUAUUUUAUAGCAUCACUUUUCAAUCUUCAAAUGAAAAUCAUGGAUGAUGAAGCUUACCUUCACUCAUAAAAACAUCACUCCAUUUACUAUUCUGAAAUGAAACUAGCAGGUAAUAUAACUAGCCUCUAAAACAUACCCAUCAGUGACGUUCUAACUGAAACAGAUAAGAUAUUUUAUAAUGAAAUAAUUAUUUUCAUAUGUACAUAUUCUAGCAUGGUUAUAUUACAAGAUGUAAUUAAACUACUAAGCAGGGCACAUACUUUGUAUGUGUGUGUAUAAAUAUAAAUAUGUGAAAAAUCACCAUGAAUGUGGUAGUUACCAAUUCAGACCUGCUGCAUUGGCAGUUCAAUACCAGGAAAGGGGUCGAUGUCAGCAGUAUGAUUUUCUAAAAUGUGGCCAAUUCUUUAGAUAAAGUUCUAGGCAUACCUAGUCUGUAAUGGCUUCACUCAUAUAGUGCUUGCUGUGUGCCUGGCAUUGUUCUAAUACCUUUCUAAUAAAUCUAUGAGGUGAGUACUGCUGUUAGUCCCGUUUUGCAUAUGAGGGAGUUACCCAGGUUAUGUGCUAGUCAUCCUGGUUAUGUGCUAAUAAUGGCAGAGCUGGGAUUAAAAUGAAAGCAGCCUGGCUCUGGCUUUCUUGCUCAUAAUCACUCAGUAUAUAGGCUUCCUUCCAUUUAUAGAAUUCUCUCAUUGCAUUCUUGAAAAAUCCAAAGCAUAUUAAAACUGGGCUGAAAAUUCUGUGUGUUUAUAUAUAAAAUGAAAUGAGAUCAUAGAUUUGUUAUUGUAAACUGAGUUCCCAUCUAUAUGAAUAUUGGGCGGGGCAAUUGAAAGUUGUGUUGAUGAGUCAGCUCUUUGUUGUGAGGGCUGUAAGCUGCAGGGCUUGUGUAUCACGCAUGCUCCAACAGGUUAAAUCUCAGUAGUGGCCGCCCAUCAGUGGCACCCCUAACAUGCUCACAUUUCCAGAACUGCCUCUUGGGCGGAGGUGGGGGAGGGUACCAUCUCUUUCAGAACAAGUAUUUUAAAAGAAAUCCUGUAUCCUCCUUAAGUAGUAUUUCAGUCUAUAUAUUUGUCCAUUUCCUAUCUCUGCUUCUCUCUCAGUUCUUUCCCCACCAAACCUGAAAUUUCAGAAUCUAUUUUGUGGGCUUUCUUUUUUUAAUUUUUUCCCUGGAAGACCAUGAACAUUCCUCUUUAGGUUGUUAGUAUUGCAGCAAACCCUGAGGUAUUGACACAAAACUUUUCAUCCGCCAAAGAGCUCGAGUAAGUAAAUCUGUCUGACAUUUGAAUGUCACCAGCAAAGCAUGAGACUCAUGCUGCCUUUUGCCACCAUAGGCAUGAAUGGUAUGGAGAAGUAGGCCUGACUUGUUUUCUUCUAUUGUAGAUGAGAUUAGUUUUGUAGACCAUUAGUUCACAUUUUGCUCCUACCCUUGUGCAUAAAAUCACUGCAUCAUUUCCGUGGGGAUGAGACUACUGCAAGCUACUUCCUUGGAGAUUCUGUGGAAGAUGGACAUCUUAAAAGUAAACUACUUUUGGUAUGACUGCUCAUUGGCUUGGCCAGUGAUACUUGAUGUUAUUUAUUUUGUGAGUUACUCUGUGUCUUAAUCAGCUCAGGCUGCAAUAACAAAAUACCAUACACUGGGUAGCUUAAAUGACAGAAAUUUCUCACCGUUCUGGAGGCUGGGAAGUCCAAGAUCAAGGUGAGUUCCUGGUGAGCACCCUUACCCUGGUUUGCUGAUAGCCAUCAUCUUCCCAUUGCAUCCUUACAUGGCAGAGAGAGAGAAAGGAAGCAAGCAAGCUCUCCUUUCCCUUCUUGUGAGGGCGCUAAUAUUCAUGAGGGCUCCACCCUCAGGACCUACUCACUUCCCAAAGGCCCACUUAUGGUAUUAGCUCCGCCUCCUAAUACCAUUGCUUUGGAGAUUAGGGUUUCAACAGAUGAAUUUUGGGAGGACAUAAACAUGCAAUCCAUAGCACUCUGCUUUUGUAUAUUUUUCAAACCUUUCAUGCUAAUCAGCUGGAAGGUGAAUAUUUUAAAAUCUAUUUUAAAACUGGCUUAAGGAGCACACAAAAGCUGAUUUCUGAUGUUUCUUCCAAUACGUGGAAAAUUUUGCAUGAUGUAUUAACCCCUAGUUAGGGUCCCUCAACCCCAGUUGAGGACCUCAACACACAUUUGGUAAUACCUAAGGGAAUUUAAAUAUAUAUUUUGUAGCCUAUAGCAUAUGGAAUUAGAAAAAAAUUAGUCUCUUUACUGUAAAAUUUACCUUUUAAUUAUUUGGAAAUUUCACAAUUGCCAAGUUUCAACUUAAAGUUUCUAUUUAUUUGGGGCCAGAAUUAUUGCCAGAAGUGUGCUAAUUUGACAAAGGGUACCUUUUACAUAAGUAAAGGAAAAAGUGAUUACAUCAUGUUCAGACCUGCUAGAGGGCCUUGUUUUUCCUCUAGUUUUAGGGGUGUGGAGUCUGUCCCAAACCCUAUAUAUGUGUGCAUUUGUGUAUGUAAAAGACAAAUUUUUUAUACUCAAAAGUUUGUCUUAAAUAAUGGCCUAUGGCCUACUGAUUUGGAUAGAGGAGAGAAAUUUUGUCUAUAAGCAACAAAAAAUGCUACACAGCCAGGAGACUGUCACACACAGUUUUUCAGAACCUUUGGGCCACAUACUGCACUCCCCUUCCAUAGAAAUACACAUGGGGUCAGUGAUUAAGGACUCAAUUCUGGUUGUGACUUGGCCAUCCAUAGGCAUAUUCUAAAGUUCUAUGGCAACCUUUAUGAAGCUCGUCUUCUGAGUUGAUCACCUGUUCAUGCGCUGCCCAUUUACAACAUACCUCAGGGAUUAAAACGUGAGGCUACACCUAAGGAAAGUCGGUCCUAAUCCUGCGUUUCCUCCUGCAUGUCACUGACCAUUGGAGUCACUGCUCUCUGAGGAAGACAGUUUACAGCCUGAGCAUUCAUGUCACGCUCACAGCCAACCUGUUACUUGCUGGCCUCCUUUACCAAGCUCCUUGUUUCAUGAAGAAGUUGUGAAACUGAAGUUGGAGGAAAAAAAUUAAGAAAUAAACCUCAAAGGUAUUUAAAAGGGCAGUAGAGUAAUUACUCCUCACACCCAGGGAUAAGGAUAUUCUCAUCAUUUUCUCUCCUCUUGCCUGGAGCAUAAACAUUCAGAUGUUUGUGAAGAAAUGAUUAAAAGGAGAGAAAAUAUCAGGAGAAAAAUGAUUAAAAUGAGAGAAAUGUUCUUCCACUGACUAGACCCAUUAAAGGGGAGGAUUUAACUUUAUUGUUAGAGGGGUGAAAACUGGAUUUUAAGAUAUUUCUUCACCAUUUUGACAUAUCUUGGGCUGAACAUUUUGAUUAUUUUAGAGAAUCAGGGAGCUUCAGAAAUGAAGUUUAAUAUAAAGUAAGAUUGUCUCUGAAGGAAGAAAUUGUCCUUUUAACUCAGUGUCAGGUUCCGUUUUCUUACUCAUAUCUAAACUUCCUGUCACUCCAACUGAGGCUGCACCAGGAUAAGAGGAGGGAUUUGAGGAAUUAGCGCGAAUUUAGAAGCCUUUGACUUUUGGGAAUUUGCAUCAAGCAGAUAGAAGCAGGCGGGGGCUCAGCUUUUGAAGUUGGAUCAUCCAGCUGUCUCACUUUGCCACUUAUGGGAUCUGUGACUUGAAGCAGGUGACUGACCUCUCCACUCCUCAGUUAUCUAUGAAAUGGGGAUAAUACUAGCAUCUACUUCGAAGGCUUAUGGUGAUUAAAUGAGAUAAUGUUUUUAAGGCCCUUUCUUCGCAUAGUCUGGCACACAGCAUUUAAGAGAUGUUGACUCGUGUUCCUGUAGUAGCAGUACUGACUCCAUCUCAGCCUCUAGUGAAUAAGGUAUUCAGAGCUGGCCAACAGGAAAUUGCUCAUUCUUUUGUCCAUAAGCAGCAAAAUAAUGCCAGUGUGACACUGUCAGAGGGCUGCAGUGUGGUCAGUGGCCUAGAGAUGCAGCUUUUACUGUUAGAAAACUCACUCGGAUGUUUUAGCCGAUUCAGAACUCAAGAAAUGACAAAAGUCUGUGAUUGGACACACUUUUUUUUUUUUUUUUGAGACGGAGUUUCAGUCUUGUUGCCCAGGCUGGAGUGCAAUGGUACGAUCUUGGCUCACCGCAACUUCCGCCUACUGGGUUCAAGUGAUUCUCCUGCCUCAGACUCCCAAGUAGCUGGGAUUACAGGCAUGUGCCACCACACCCGGCUAAUUUUGUAUUUUUAGUAGAUGGGGUUUCUUCGUGUUGGUCAGGCUGGUCUCGAACUCCCGACCUCAGGUGAUCCGCUCACCUCAGCCUCCCAAAGUGUUGGGAUUACAGGCGUGAGCCACUGCGCCCCGCCUAGAGUAUUCUUUCAAUAUUGACUUGAUUUGUCAUCAUCAUAUCUUUUCUAUUAAAUCCCUUCCACUUCCUUCAAUGAAAUCGUAUAUGAAAACAAAGGGAAUCGGAGCAUUUUGCCCACCUCCUAGUUGGCUGAAUUAUUUUUGCCUCCCAUUCCCAUCUUGAAGUGGUAUUCCUCAAACUCGUUUCUAUGUUUCCUGUGGUUUUAAAUAAAGGAAUAAUGUAGAAUGGUAUCUAUUUUGGACAUUCUCAUCGUGAAAAGGAACUCUUACACAAAUACAAAGCCAAGAGAUUGUGUUGCCAUUGUUGAAGCUGAAAAGGACAGUCACUGGAUGCCUCCCCACCCAAGGCCAAGGCUUUGGUAGGUCCAGGAAGUGAAAAGGAAAGAGAAGCUAUGGGAGAGACAAAGGGAAGUAAAAAAUGGUUGUUCGGCUCAGCAUAACAAUCACUUUUGUGGGGCUUAUUGGUUGUGCAUAAAUUUCAUCCAUUUGGGCACACACACAGAUGUGACACCCAGACCACUCAGACACUUGGCUAACACUGAUGCCGUCAUCCUGAAUGUUGUUUCUGGAAGGACUUUCAUGAAUAGAAUCUAUUUCAGAUUGGCCGUAAGUCUCGAUUUAUUGAUCCGCACCACUGGACUGGGGUGGGGUUGUGUCCACUUUUUCCCUGCCCCUUCCCUGCUUUGGCUCUUGUGAUUGUGUCCUCCGUGUGUCAGGCAGAGCCCUGUGAAGGUGUGGAUAUGUGGCCAUAUUUUACCUGCAUAAUCUGCAGUUCAUAUGAUUCAGCCUAAUGGGUUGCAAUGCCCUGAGGACAGAGACCAUACUUUUUCUUCCUUUGUCUUUUUAGCGAAAUUCAAUCCUGUUCUGCGCCUGCGCCACAGUUGCAGGCUGUACUGUCUGCCCUGUGCAUCUCACACACCCCCACUGCACUGUGCACCUAGUGAUGGCCGCAGAUUUGCUUUUACUCAUCUUCCAGGGCCUACCCUGUUAAUUCCAUCACAGUUGCAGGCUGUACUGUCUGCCCUGUGCAUCUCACACACCCCCACUGCACUGUGCACCUAGUGAUGGCCGCAGAUUUGCUUUUACUCAUCUGUUUGCAGGGCCUACCCUGUUAAUUCCAUCACAGUUGCAGGCUCUACUGUCUGCCCUGUGCAUGCAUCUCACACACCCACUGGACUGUGCACCUAGUUGAUGACCACAGAUUUGCUCUUACCCAUCUAUUUCCAGGGCCUGCCACUGUUAAUUCCUAGGAAAAAAGAAAAAACAAGCAUGGUGGAUUGGUUAAAUUGGCAUUUUAUAUUGUUUGUGUUCAUGGCCAUGCCAAUGAUAAACAAGAGCUGGUCAUGGGCAUUCAGAUCAGAUGAGCAAUUAAAUCCCCUCCAAAAAACAGAAACCUACUUUUAGAGAAGAAAAGAAUUAAACCAAGAUCUUUCAGGGUUUUGCUUCUCCUUUUGUUUUUAAGGCACUUAAAUAAAUGGAAGAACAUGUAAGCUAACCGUGUUUAGAGUACUAUGUUUUACUAGAAAGUGCUACCCUUCUGCAGAUUUCUCCUCAAUGAAAGAAUGCCACUGAAGCACCUUUAAUGGUGCCUUUAUCCUAUAGUCUUAUUGAAUCAUUCUCUUUAGCCAACAUAAAAUACAAAGCCAGGGUAUAAGACUUCAUGUAGGUGGUAAUUUAAACUAACAAUUAGUGAGGCCGGGCGCGGUGGGUCACGCCUGUAAUCCCAGCACUUUGGGAGGCUGAGGCAGGUGGAUCACAAGGUCAGGAGAUCGAGACCAUCCUGGCUAACACGGUGAAACCCCGUCUCUACUAAAAAUAUAAAAAAAAAAAAAUUAGCCGGGCGUGGUGGCGGGCGCCUGUAGUCCCAGCUACUCGGGAGGUUGAGGCAGGAGAAUGGCGUGAACCCGGGAGGCGCAACUUGCAGUGAGCCGAGAUUGCGCCACUGCACUCCAGCCUGGGAGACAGAGCGAGACUCCGUCUCAAAAAAAAAAAAAAAAGAAAACAAUUAGUGAAUUUUUGCUGAUGCUUUCCUUAAACCCCUUACUUAGCACUUAGUUCUGGAUUCUUAAAUCCUGAUAAUGGACUCAUCCUUCUCGGUCUAGUUACCCCAGUAAGUCCCAAGGUCAUCCAUAUGAGGUCCUCCUUGAUCUUACUCUGAAUAGAAUUAACUGGUCUCUUCUGUUUUUCCAUAGCAUUGACUCAUCGUGUUAGACCAGCUUGAAUUGUGAGCCUUUCUAAAGCAGGGUCUGUAUAAUUUACCCUUAUAUUUGCUCUGUAGGCAGAGAAAAUAUUAUUGAAGUAACUAGAUGGUAAAAUUAACUGUGCAAUCAGAAAAGAAGUUAGAAAAAAUUAUUAAAAUUUUCUGUGAAAAUUGUUUUAAUUUUAUUAAUAUAUUAAAGCAUUUUGCAGACUAUUCCAUAAAGAAUUUUAUUACAUUGGCUCUCAUUUUAAAGAAAACAUUAUACCAGGUGUCAGAACUCAAUCAUAUUUGUAGGAAGAAUAAGCCUUGGCCAUCAACAACGCUUCUUUGGUUACAGGAUUACAGGAACUGCUGAGAAUGUAAGCACUUUCCGAAGUCCACAAAGAACUCAUUUAAAGCUCGUACAGGCAGUUUCAAAUUAGCCAGGGAAAAGUUAAUGGUGGGGAGGUAAGGUCAUAGAAUGCUCUAUAAAUGGAGGCGACGUGGAGGACAGUUGCAGUUGUAUAACAUUUGAUUGAAGGAGAGGGAUUUGGACCUGAGGAAACCAGGUCUAUAAAUACUAAGGCUGGCUGGGCACAGUUGGCUCAUGCCUGUAAUCUCAGCAUUUUGGGAGGCUGAGGCCGGUGGAUUGCUUGAGCCCAGGAGUUUGAGACCAGCCUGGACAACAUGGUGAAACCCUGCCUCCAAACAAACAAAAUUAACCGAGUGUGGUGGUGUGCACCUGUAGUCCCAGCUACUCAGGAGGCUGAGAUGGGAGGAUCUCUUGAGCCUGAGAGGUAGAGGCUGCAGUAAGCCCAGAUUGCACCACUGCACUCCAGCCUGGUGACAGAGUGAGACUCCAUCUCAAACAAACAAAACGUACAUGCAUAUAUAGGCUGUAGACUAAAUAGUGAAAUAUUACUAAGAACCUUCAUCCCAAGGGGUUGAGUGGUAGAACCACUGAGAAUAUUGUUGCUGCUCUUUUGGAGACAACAAACUGCAUUAAUAAAAGUCUGAGAACAAGAAAGUUGAGUUUUCAAGUAAUGUCCUUUGCAUAUUGCUACAUAGGGCUCAUCUGAGUCUGUGAUGUUCUACUUUGUUGAUGAAAGAAAACAAGUGGAAAUUCUGCUCCCCCACACAUCCUGCACUGCAAAAAGAUAACAAGUAGCAGGAGAUACUCAAUUAUGAUGCAGUUCAACAAAGAAAACAAAUUAAAAUAAAGAGAUCCUGGGUGGUUAAAUACAGAGUCUCCUUUGUAAACAGCAAUGGAUGAUGAUGAUGACUGUUACCAGGGCUCUGUAUGAUCAUUUUCCCAAUUCUUUGGAGUACUUUUUUCAAAAGCACUCUUGUAGAAUUAACUGGAAACAUAGACUACCCUUCACUCAUUACAUGGGAAAUGGGAUUGAAUUCUCUUCUUGGCAAUGGAAAAUACUUGAUGCAUGCAAAUAAGAAAACUCUUACUUUUUCCUUCUCUCCUUGCAGGGGGAGCACGCGUCCUAAGCUUGCCAGGAAGCCCUGCUCUCCUGCCCUGGGCACCUCCGUUCCACUUGACCUUUUCCACCUGUACUCCCUGCAUUUUGGUCUCUUGCUCUGGUCUUUAGCCUUCGCAUUUUCCUGAUGCAGCCCAAACCAGUCACCUCUCUCCUAGAUUCAUUCUCUGUGCUCAGACCAUCUCUUUCCUUUAGUUCCUGUGACGAAAGAAAAUGUAUUUGGCCAUUGGAGGUAUAAGCAACAAAGAAUCCAACCCACACAGCUUUAUAUAUGCAGGUUCUCUAUAUGCUCUUCUUGUGAACAGCGUGGGGAGAGGAAAAUAGACUUGGCAAGAGGACUAAGAACAGAAUCGGACAGUUAUCUGAUGGCUUUCCUAAGGUUCAGGAAAGAACAGUGGUCCCUUUGUUGGGCCUUUCUGUUGUUUCUUUGUUUUCAAUUUCACUGAUUUCUGCUUUUUAUUUUCUAUUUUCUUCUGUUUCCUUUGGAAUUCUUCUUUUUUUUUUUUUUUUUUUUUACUUCUUGUAUUAGGCUCAUGCUAUAACAAACAACCCCCAAAUCUCAGUGACUUUACACACUAAGAGUUUACAUUUUCCUCAUCAACGUCCACUUUGGAUGUUCCAGGUUGGGUAAUGCUCUGUGGCUGUCCUCUAGCUAGUGACUCAGGGACUUGGGUUGCUCCUGGUGUCUCCAGCGUGGUUAUGGUGUCUCCAAUUUUGGACUUCAAGGUGACCCAGGCAUUAUCCACCUGGUAAAUUGGGAGAUGGGUCCCAGGAAAGUGAAUACUCAACCAACCUGGCCUAGAAGUGACAAUAAUAAGGCCAUGUGUGGUGGCUAACAGUCAGAAACCCAACAAUUGGGAGAUUGAGCUGGGAGGAUUGCUUGAGACCAGAAGUUCAAGACCAGCUGGGCACCAUAGUGAGACCCUAUCUUUCAAAAAAAUAUAACAACCAGGCUUGGUGGUGUACACCUGUGGUCCCAGCUAUUUGGGAGGCUGAGGUGGGAUAAUCGCUGGAGCCCAGGAGUUUGAGGUUACAGUAAACCAGGUUUACACCACUGCACUCCAGUCUGGAUGACAAAGCAAAACCCUCAUCUCACAAAAGAAAAGAAAUGACAAUCACAGCCACUGCAACUUCAAGGAAGGUUGGGAGAGUGAUAUUGGUCAGGAUGAGUGGUCUCUGACAUGUUUCUUAAGUUGGAUAUUUAGCUUAUUAAUUUACAACUCUUUUCUAAUAUUAAUACUCAAGACUACAUUUUCCCCAAAACAUUUAUUUUGCCAUGUUUUGCAAGGCUUGGUAUAUGGCAUUUUCAUUACUCUUUAAUUCUAACUAAUUUUUAAUUUCUAUUAUGAUUUAUUAUUUGAUCUAUGAAUCAUUUUGAAAUUUGUUUUUGUAACCUUGGAUAGGGAAAGAUUUCUUAUAGAAGACAGUAAAAGGGCUGAGUACAAAAGAAAAGACUAAUAAAUUCAGCUACGCUAAAGCUUAGAACUUUUCCUCAUCAUAGGACACCUUAAAGAAAAUUUUUAAAAAGUUACAAAUUGGGAGAAGAUUAAAAAGUCCUAAGGGUUAGCAGUAAGAAUAUAUACAUAUAAUUAUUACAAAUUGGCAAGAGAAUGACAAAUCAACACAAAAACGAGCGAAAAGGCAUUUUGCAAAAGAGAAUCAGAUGGUCCAUAUGCAUGUGAAGCGAUUUUCACUAGCGAGCAGGGAAAGUGAAGUCAAAAUCACAGGGAGAUGCUGCUCUCUACCUGACUGGCAAAACUGAAAUGAUUAGAAAAUACUUGGAGGAUAUCCUAGAACGAUCAGUGGGAUCUGGUAUAUUAUGUGUAUGAGGUUAAAUUAGCAGUGAGUAUUCACAUACCCUAUGACUCAGCAGUUUCAUUCCUAGAUAUAUAUCCUGGGGAUUAGAAACACUAAGUAGGUGGGUGCAGUGGCUCACACCUACAAUCCCAGCACUUUGGGAGGCCAAGGCAGGUGGAUCACUUGAGGUCAGGGGUUCGAGACCAGACUGGCCAACAUGGUGAAACCCCAUCUCUACUAAAAAUACAAAAAUUAGCCAGGCGUGGUGGCGGGCACCUGUAAUCCCAGCUACUUGGGAGGCUGAGGUGGGAGAAUCGCUUGAACCCCGGAGGUGGAGGUUGCAGUGAGCUGAGAUUGUGCCACUGUACUCCAGCCUGGGCGACAGAAUGAGACUCCAUCUCCAAACAAACAAACAAACAAACAAACCACUAACUACCUCAGAGGACAAUGCUAACAUUUCAAAGUGUUCUAGAAGUUGGUUUCCCAGAAAAGAAGUCAGGCUCUUGUGGAGCUCCAUGGAAACUGGCAAUGACCCAUGACUUAGGGCAGUGAAGUCUCAUCAAAUGCAAGGCUUAGACCCCAUUCUGCUGCUGCCGUCAGGGGAGGCAAGGGCUCCUUGUUCCCCAAACAUCGAUGCUAAUGAAGCAAAUCCUGCUGCUAGUUUGCAGUGUUGCCUAGCUGCAAACACAACCUCUGAUGAUGCCAAUAGAGAGGCUGGUGCCUCCUUCAUCAUAGAGCUUACAAUCCCCACAAGGUUUCGGGACCCUCUUUUGGAUUCUGAGGGUGGGCUCCUUUAGCCAUCUGUUUAGUGCCCCAGAUGAAAUUGACAGCAGGGGACCUGCACUCCUUCUACUGCUUUUUCUCAAGGCAUCCCCAGCAGAGGGUCUCUAGGGUGCCUGUUAUGUGUGCUGUUUGGCCAUCUGCCUUUGUAGAACACAGCCCAAUGUCUGUUGGCAAAAAAAGGUUUACAUGUGGUAUAUUCUUACCAUGGAAUAUUCUGCAGCAAGUAAAAAUGAAUAAAUUACAGCUAUUCAUAUCAAAGAGAUGGAUUUUAUUAAUAUAGUGCUGAGUGGGAAAAAGCAUCAGAAGACAACAUAUAAUGGUACACUCUUUUUUUUUUUUUGAGAUGGAGUCUCUCUCUGUUGCCCAGGCUGGAGUGCAGUGGCUCCAUCUCGGCUCACUGCAACCUCCACCUCCCAGGUUCGAGCGAUUCUCCUGCCUCAGCUGCCCGAGUAGCUGGGACUACAGGUGCGCACCACCACACCAAGCUAAUUUUUGUAUUUUUAAUAGUGACGGGGUUUCACCAUGUUGGCCAGGAUGGUCUCUGUCUCUUGACCUCAUGAUCCGCCUGCCUCAGCCUUCCAAAGUGCUGGGAUUACAGGCAUGAGCCACCAUGCCCAGCUACAUUCUUUUUAAACAUUCAGAAACAGGUAAAACUGAAAAAUAUAUAAUUUAGACACAACACUUAUGUGAAAAGACCAAGUUUAGGAUGUUGGUUACCUGUGACGGGGCAGCAAGAUUGUGGGAAAGGAAGGAAGCUACAGGUAUGUGACAGAGAGUUGCAUUAGCCCAAAUCUCUACAGAGCUGGUGUCAAGGAUGAAACUAUUGGUGUUUUAUUUGGAAGAUACAAGCCCAAGGCGAGGUGAGAAAAAAGAGAAGGGAAGCAAAAGAAGACACAAAGUGACACAAAAUGGCAUGAACUAAAUUACGUUCUCUCCAAAUUCACAUAUUGAAGUCCUAACCCCAGUACCUCAGAAUGUAACUGUAUUUGGAGAUUCGGUCUUUAAAGAAGUGAUUCAGGCUGGGCCUGAUUGCUCACGCCUGUAAUCCCAGCACUUUGGGAGGCCGAGGCAGGCGGAUCAUGAGGUCAGGAGAUUGAGACUAUCCUGGCUAACACGAUGAAACCCUGUCUCUACUAAAAAUACAAAAAAUUAGCCAGUUGUGGUGGCAGGCGCCUGUAGUCUCAGCUACUUGGGAAGUUGAGGGAGGAGAAUGGUGUGAACCCAGGAGGUGGAGCUUGCAGUGAGCCGAGAUUGUGCCACUGCACUCCAGCCUGGGUGACAGAGUGAGACCCCGUCUCAAAAAAAGAAAAAAAGUGAUUCAGUUAAAAUGCAGUCAUUAUGGUGGGCUCAAUCAAGGACAUGUGGACACAGAUAUGUAUGCACAUGGAGGAAAGACCAUGUGAAGUCGGGGAGAAGAAAACCAGCUACACACUAAAGAAAGAGGCGUCAGGCCGGGCGCGAUGGCUCCCGCUUGUAAUCCUAGCAGUUUGGGAGGCCAAGGUGGGCAAAUCACUUGAGGUCAGGAGUUCGAGACCAGCCUGGCCAGAAUGGUGAAACCCUCUCUCUACUAAAAAUAUAAAAAUUAGCUGGGCGUGGUGGCAUGUGCCUGUAAUCCCAGCUACUUGGGAGGCUGAGGCAGGAGAAUCACUUGAACCCGGGAGGUGGAGGUUGCAGUGAGCCGAGAUGGAGCCACUGCACUCCAGCCUGGGCAACAGAGUGAGACUCCAUCUCAAAAAAAAAAAAAAAAAAAAGCCUCAGAAGAAACCAGUGCUGCUGACACCUUGAUCAGUCUUCCACCUGCAGAGCUGUGAGAAGACACAUUUCUGUUGUUUAAGCUACCCAGUCUGUGGUAUUUUGUUAUGGCAGCCCCAACAAACUAAUACACAAAAUGAUGCACAGCCUUGCUGACUAUCACUUCAAAAUGAGCCAAACAGAGACACAACGGGGCACUAGGCAAUUGUGUCCCACUCAGUGAAACUUCUCUGGAAAGCUGUAAGGUAUAGUCCAGAGACGAGAGGAAGGGAAGAAGAAAUUUAUCCUCUGGGAGCCUCCCAUUUCCUGUCUCCUAAUAGUGAGAAUUUUUCCAUGAGAAGUUAAUGUCCCUAUACUUUCACAAUGUGUUACCUUCUUUUGUUGCUGUUCAAGAUGCCAAGCCUAUGCCCUGCAGUGUGGCCUUUUGUCAGAGUCCAUAAAGGGCAGGAGGAACUAGGAACUCUGGGUGUGUAUGGUUGGCCCAGCUGCAGAGUUGACAGUCAAGGGGAUAACCAACUCUAAUCAGCCUAGAAGGGAACUUGGUAGCCUAGGUGAGUUGGUCAGGCACAGGCUGGGGCUAAGGCAAGGCAAAUGGCUGAGGUCUAAGACGUAGGUGGUGCUGAGAAAAUGUGGGGAAGCAUACAAGAUUUGUGACUGAUGAGUAAUAUUCUAGUUCUUGGUUAGGAUAAUGGGUACAUGGGGUGUUCCUUUUAUUAUUUUCAAAAUGAAAUGAAAUAAAAGAGGGAUAUGUGUGGACUGAUGAUGAUGUAUAAUGAAUCAAAGAUUAUGAUUAACUUAACUCUGCAUACUUGAGUUUGUUUAUUUUUCUAUAAAAGGAGAAUAGCAAUAUUAAGUCUUACAGCCCAGGAAUGAAAUGUCUUUCCAUUUGUUUGUGUCUUCUUUAAUUUAUUUCAUCAGUAUUUUGUAGUUUUCAGUAUACAAGUCUUUCACCUCCUUAGUUAAGUUUAUUCCCAAGUAUUUUAUUAUUUUGGGUGCUAUUAUAUAUGGGAUUGUUUCGCUAAUUUCCUUUUUAGAUAGUUCUGUGUUAAUGUAUAGAAAUCGCAACUGAUUUUUGUAUGUUGAUUUUGUAUUAUGCAACUUUAUUGAAUUCCUUUAUUCUAACAUGUUUAAAAAAUGGAGUCUUAGGGCGUUCUAUAUAUGAGACGAUGUCAUCUGAAGACAGGGACAAAACAAUUCUACAGUCCAUAUGAAACCACAAAAGACCAUGAAUAGCCAUAUCAAUCUUGAGAAAGAAGAACAAAGAUAGAGGCAUCACAUUGCUUGAUUUCAGAAUGUAUAACAAAACUACAGUAAUCAAAACAGUAUGUUACUGGCCAACAGAUAGACAUAUAUGUGAAUGGAACAGAAUAGAGAGUCCAGAAAUAGAUUCACAUGUAUAUUGUCAACUGAUCUUCAACAAUGGUGCCAAGAAUACAUAAUGGGGAAAGGAUAGUCUCUUCAACACAUGGUAUUGAGAAAAUCAGAUAUCCAUGUGCAAAAGGGGGAAACUGGACUUUUAUCUUACAUCACAUACAAAACCCAACUCAAAAUGGAUUAAAGAUUUAAACAUAAAAUCUGAAGCUGUAAAACUCCUAGAAGAAAACAUAGGCGAAAAGCUCUUUGACAUUGGUCUUGUCAAUGAUUUCAUGGAUAUGACCCCCAAAACACAGGCAACAAAAACAAAAAUAAGCAAAGUUACAUCAAAUCACAAAGCUUCUCACAGCAAAGGCAACAAUCAACAGAGUGAAAAGAAAACCUAUGAAAUGGGAGAAAGUAUUUGCAAGCGAUGUAUGUGAUAAGGGUUGACAUCUAAAAUAUGUAAGGAAUUCAUAACUCAAUAGCAAAAAAAAAAAAACCCAAUUUUUACAAAUGGGCCAAGGAUCUGAAUAGCAUGGGCUCUGGCAUCUUGAACAGCAAUGAAAGAAGCUAGUUGACACAUUGCGAGAGUAUAGGGAUAUUAACCUCUCAUGGGCAAAUUCUCAUCAAUGAGAGGAAAUGGGAGGCUCCCAGAGGAUAAAAGGUGCUCAUCAUCACUGAUCAUCAGGGCAAUGCAAAUCAAAACCACCGUGAGAUAUCAACUCUCACCUGUCAGGAUGGCUAUCAUUGAAGAACCAAAACACAACAAAUAUUGGUGAAGAAGUGGACAAAUUGGAACCCUUGCAUACUGUUGAUGGGAAUGCAAAAUGGUGCAGCCACUAAGGAAAACAGUAUGGGUGUUCCUAAAAAAUGUAAAAAUAGAACUGCCAUGUGACCUAGCAACCCUAUUUCUGGAUAUUUAUCCAAAAAAAUUGAAAUCAGGAUCCCAAAGAGGUAUUAGCAUUUGCAGGUUCAUUGCCGCAUUAUUCACAAUAUCCAAGAUACACAAACAAUCUAAGCGUCCAUCGGCGGAGAAAUGAAUAAAGAAAAUGUAUAUACACAUACAAUGGAAUACUAUUUAGCUUUUAAAAAGAAGGAAAUUCUGCAAUUAUUCAACAACAUGGAUAAAUCUUAAGGACAUUACGCUAAGUGAAAUAAACUAUUAACAGAAAGACUAAUAUGGCAGGAUUCAAUUUAUGUGGGAUAUUUAAAAUAGUCAACUUCAUAGAACCAAAGAGUGAAAUGAUGGUGGCCAGGGGCUGAGGGGAGUGGGGAGUUACUAAUCAAUAGGCAUAAAGUUUCAGUGAAGUCAGGUGAAUAAGCUCUAGAGAUUUGUGGUACAAUAUUGCACCUAUAGUCAACAAUACUGCAGUGUACACUGAACAAUUUGUUAAGAUAGAUCUCACCUUGUGUUCUUACUGAAAAAAAAAAAGAAAGAAAAUAGAACAGAAAAGCAAUUGGAUUUUAAUUCUGGAAACUCCUUUCUCUUCCUUACAUCCAGGAAAUUUGCUGUUUAUUUUGAAAAGCAAAUUUAAACCUAUUUAAGGGAGAGAGAGCUCUUGUAAAAAUUCAUUUAUUAGUUCUGGACCAAUGUUAUUUAUAAGCUAUUAUUUCAAAUGAUAAAAAAUAAAUGCAUAAUACAUUUGAUGAUAGAACAUUUUUCUUUUUAAAUAAGGCCUGAUUUUUCAAAAAGCAUUGAAUAUGUUUGUUUCUAAUUUCCAAAGCUUGACAGUUUCUUAUGUUUCAUUAAAAGCAGAAGAAUUGUUAUGUAUGCAUGUUCAUAUCACUUUUGAAUGACUCAUGUGGCUACAAAUGCAGCAAUCUGUGGUUAUCAUGGACCAUGAACUAGAUAAACAUUCCUGCUUUUCUUAACAUUCCUUUCCUGUGCCUCAUUAACUAAUGUACAUAAUAAAACAUCUUUAUUUCA